AGUUCCCACAGCACCCCAGCGGCCUGCCAUGGGGGGUCUAAGGCCCUGGUCCCGAUACGGGCUCCUGGUUGUGGCCCACUUGCUGGCCCUGGGGCUUGGGGCUGUGGUGUUCCAGGCCCUGGAGGGGCCUCCUGCAUGCAGGCUUCAGGCUGAGCUCAGGGCAGAGCUGGCAGCCUUCCAGGCAGAGCAUAGGGCCUGCCUGCCACCCGGAGCUCUGGAAGAGCUGCUGGGCACUGCCCUGGCCACCCAGGCCCAUGGGGUCUCCACCCUGGGCAACAGCUCAGAGGGCAGGACCUGGGACCUUCCCUCAGCCCUGCUCUUCGCUGCCAGCAUCCUCACCACCACAGGUUAUGGCCACAUGGCCCCACUAUCGCCAGGCGGAAAGGCCUUCUGCAUGGUCUAUGCAGCCCUGGGGCUGCCAGCCUCCUUAGCUCUCGUGGCCACCCUGCGCCAUUGCCUGCUGCCUGUGCUCAGCCGCCCACGUGCCUGGGUAGCGGUCCACUGGCAGCUGUCACCGGCCAGGGCUGCGCUGCUGCAGGCAGUUGCACUGGGACUGCUGGUGGCCAGCAGCUUUGUGCUGCUGCCAGCGCUGGUGCUGUGGGGCCUUCAGGGCGACUGCAGCCUGCUGGGGGCCGUCUACUUCUGCUUCAGCUCGCUCAGCACCAUUGGCCUGGAGGACUUGCUGCCCGGCCGCGGCCGCAGCCUGCACCCCGUGAUUUACCACCUGGGCCAGCUCGCACUUCUUGGUAAGUCCAGCCACCUAACAGCGUGUGGGGGAAGGGGGAAGAGGAGCCUGGACUAGGACUCCCAUAAAUCACUGGGGGGCUGGGCCUUGCAGGUGGAGGGACCUCACUCCAGGGCACGGCGUGGGAGGGGUAGUCGAAGAGCUCUGGUGGCAGCGUUGAGAAGGGGGUGAGUGGUGCCAGUUGCCAGGGCAAGUCACUGCGCUGGGAGGUGGGCGGGGAGCAUCACCAGAACCCAGGCGCUGCCCCAGCACCUUCUCCUCCCCAGGUUACUUGCUUCUAGGACUCUUGGCCAUGCUGCUGGCAGUGGAGACCUUCUCUGAGCUGCCGCAGGUCCGUGCCAUGGGGAAGUUCUUCAGACCCAGUGGUCCUGUGACUGCUGAGGACCAAGGUGGCAUCCUAGGGCAGGAUGAACUGGCUCUGAGCACCCUGCCGCCCGCGGCCCCAGCUUCAGGACAAGCCCCUGCUUGCUGAAGCGUCAGGUGACCGAGUUCAGCUCCGUAAGGUGGCGGCACCUGAGGAGGAAGCAGCCAGGAGUGGCUGGGGAAGAAUCUGGAGAUGGAGCCGCGGUGAGGGUGGGCGGGAGGCCUCAGAGGAUACUGUUAAUCAUAAAAUGAGCAACGACUUCGGCUAUUUUCAACUA